GCAUUGCCGUUUUUGCUCAGAAUCGCGACUAAGGCUUUUUUUUUUUCUCCCUCUGAACGGUUAGGCUAUGGCUGCGAUAAAGGCCGUCAACUCCAAGGCUGAGGUGGCGCGGGCCCGGGCAGCUUUGGCUGUCAAUAUAUGCGCCGCCCGAGGGCUGCAGGAUGUGCUGCGGACCAACUUGGGUCCUAAAGGCACCAUGAAAAUGCUUGUUUCUGGUGCAGGUGACAUCAAACUCACCAAAGAUGGCAAUGUGCUGCUCGAUGAGAUGCAAAUUCAACAUCCAACAGCUUCCUUGAUAGCAAAAGUAGCAACAGCUCAGGAUGACGUCACAGGAGAUGGUACUACUUCAAAUGUUCUAAUUAUUGGAGAGUUAUUAAAACAAGCUGACCUGUACAUUUCUGAGGGCCUGCACCCUAGAAUAAUAGCUGAAGGAUUUGAAGCUGCAAAGAUAAAAGCACUUGAAGUUUUGGAGGAAGUUAAAGUGACAAAGGAGAUGAAAAGAAAAAUCCUCUUAGAUGUAGCUAGAACAUCAUUACAAACUAAAGUUCAUGCUGAACUGGCUGAUGUCUUAACAGAGGUUGUGGUGGAUUCUGUUUUGGCUGUUAGAAGACCAGGUUACCCUAUUGAUCUCUUCAUGGUAGAAAUAAUGGAGAUGAAGCAUAAAUUAGGAACAGAUACAAAGUUGAUCCAAGGAUUAGUUUUGGAUCAUGGUGCCCGUCAUCCAGAUAUGAAGAAGCGAGUAGAAGAUGCAUUUAUCCUUAUUUGCAACGUUUCACUGGAAUAUGAAAAAACAGAGGUGAACUCUGGUUUCUUUUAUAAGACUGCAGAAGAGAAAGAGAAAUUGGUAAAAGCUGAAAGAAAAUUUAUUGAAGAUAGAGUACAAAAAAUAAUAGACCUGAAGGACAAAGUCUGUGCUCAGUCAAAUAAAGGAUUUGUCGUCAUUAAUCAAAAGGGAAUUGAUCCAUUUUCCUUAGAUUCUCUUGCAAAACAUGGAAUAGUAGCUCUUCGCAGAGCAAAAAGAAGAAAUAUGGAAAGACUCUCUCUUGCUUGUGGUGGAAUGGCCGUGAAUUCUUUUGAAGAUCUCACUGUAGAUUGCUUGGGACAUGCUGGUCUUGUGUAUGAGUAUACAUUAGGUGAAGAAAAGUUCACUUUUAUUGAGGAGUGUGUUAACCCUUGCUCUGUUACCUUGUUGGUUAAAGGACCAAAUAAGCAUACUCUCACACAAGUCAAGGAUGCCAUAAGAGAUGGACUUCGUGCUAUCAAAAAUGCCAUUGAAGAUGGUUGUAUGGUUCCUGGAGCUGGUGCAAUUGAAGUGGCAAUGGCUGAAGCUCUUGUUACAUAUAAGAACAGUAUAAAAGGAAGAGCUCGUCUUGGAGUCCAAGCUUUUGCUGAUGCCUUACUCAUUAUUCCCAAGGUUCUUGCUCAGAAUGCUGGUUAUGACCCACAGGAAACAUUAGUAAAAGUUCAGGCUGAGCAUGUCGAGUCAAAACAACUUGUGGGCGUAGAUUUGAAUACAGGUGAGCCAAUGGUAGCAGCAGAUGCAGGAGUUUGGGAUAAUUAUUGUGUAAAAAAACAACUUCUUCACUCUUGCACAGUGAUUGCCACCAACAUUCUCCUGGUUGAUGAAAUUAUGCGAGCUGGGAUGUCUUCUCUCAAAUGAUGAUUGAAUUCAAAAUCAACCCUUCUAGAAGAUGAAAUUUAGUACACUUUACAUCUGACUACUAUUGUGUAGCCUGAGCCAUUCUGAAUUUCUACACAAUAAAUGCAGUUUAUGUCUUUUGGGUCUUAAUAGUCUCAAAAAUAUUUCAUCAAGGUAUAAAGAACACAAUAAAUACUUUUACAGUAAA